ACCUCAGCCUCCCAAAUUGCUAGGAUUACAGGCAUGAGCCACUGCGCCCAGCCCUCAAAUUUUGUCUUCUAUGGGGCAGAACCUGAGAGUGACAGUGAAGCAAGAAUAUCCCUCAGUUAUAAGCGAAUGAGGUUUAGCGCCAAGAGAUCAUUUUACCAGCUUAAUUGAGAGGCAGUAUUGCUCAGUGAUUGCAGGCAGUAGAGUCAAGUGAUAGGAGGCAGAGUGGCUGAGUUAGGCUCUUGAUUUACACCACCUGGUUUCCUCUCCUAGCUCUACCACUCACUGUUUGCCUUUGGGCAAGUCACUUAACCUCUCUGUGCUUCUGUUGCCUCAUCUGUAACAUGGAGAUAAUAAUGCUACCUAUCUCAUAAGGUUGUUGCCGGUAGUAACCGGAGUUUACUUUGCAGAAAGGGCUUAGAACAAUGAGUAAAACCAAGGACGUGCAAUAUGAGUGUUCAUCAUCCUCUUCUCUUGAUCAUUUUUUGACAAGAAGGAGGGCAACAGACAGGCUUCCAGAGCUCCGUUCCAGACACAGGAUGCUGAAGACAUGCUCCGUAGUUGUAUGGAGCAGAGAGACUUUGCAGUUCCUCAAUAAUGGGGGUUUAUUCUAAAGACAUCUGUAGAAACAGGGAAAUUAGAAAACUAGGCUACAUGGCCACACUCAGAGAGUCCAAGUGAAAGCCCUACAAAGAGGUUCAUGGCAGGGGCAGGGGGCCAGGACCCAGACAGUGAACAGGCAUCAUGGAGAGAGAAACUGGAGCCUGAGAGCUCCUGGGAGCUGGAGAGCUGGCUCUGUGGUCACUGCCCCCAGGAAUCCACCAUUAGGGGGCCUCAGCAAAUGCAUCCCCAAGUCUUGGCUCUCUUGGGAGGACCUUCUGGCCAUUUCCUGUUGCUAGCUUCCUCUUUCCCUUGCCUUUCCGUCGGACAUCUUUGAUCUGCUGUCUGGAUUGUAAAAGAUGCUGGCUGUGCUUUUCCUACUCUGUAGACGUUACAAUGUUGCUGUGUGAGGGCCACUUCCACCAGCCAGCAUCCACAUGCCUAUGUGCCUGGAAACUCUCUCCUGUGCCUGGAGAGGUGGGAGGCAGCUAUAAUCUUGGCGGAAUGAAUACCUACUAGGAGCAACCUUCAUCCAAUGACUAACAGGAGCUGGGGUAUCAAUUCCCCAGCUCCCAGUGCUCAGGUCAUUCCUGCACAGGACAGUCCACCAUGGCCUCAGAUCACCAGACCCAGGCGGGCAAGCCACAGUCCCUCAACCCCAAGAUCAUCAUCUUUGAGCAGGAAAACUUUCAAGGCCACUCGCAUGAGCUCAAUGGGCCCUGCCCCAACCUGAAGGAAACUGGCGUGGAGAAGGCAGGUUCUGUCCUAGUGCAGGCUGGACCCUGGGUGGGCUAUGAACAGGCCAACUGCAAGGGCGAGCAGUUUGUGUUUGAGAAGGGUGAGUACCCCCGCUGGGACUCAUGGACCAGCAGCCGAAGGACGGACUCCCUCAGCUCCCUGAGGCCCAUCAAAGUGGACAGCCAAGAGCACAAGAUCAUCCUCUAUGAAAACCCCAACUUCACCGGGAAGAAGAUGGAAAUCAUAGAUGACGAUGUACCCAGCUUCCACGCCCAUGGCUACCAGGAGAAGGUGUCAUCUGUGCGGGUGCAGAGUGGCACGUGGGUUGGCUACCAGUACCCCGGCUACCGUGGGCUGCAGUACCUGCUGGAGAAGGGAGACUACAAGGACAGCAGCGACUUUGGGGCCCCUCACCCCCAGGUGCAGUCCGUGCGCCGUAUCCGCGACAUGCAGUGGCACCAACGUGGUGCCUUCCACCCCUCCAACUAGUGCCCUCCCCACCAUGCCUCCUUCCCAGGACCCAGGUCUGCUGCCCAGGAACCCUCCAGACCUCCCAGAGAGUGAAUAAAGUGUGACUUGCAACUUG